AGAUUCUCGCAAAUCUGGAAGCGGAUCGCGUGGAGUGACGGUCACACCGCGGCGAAUUAAUUUCCAAAGACUCAUGUUACAUGAGAAAGCCACCAAGAAGACCAAAGAAAAGGAGACAAGGAUGGCUCUUCCUCAGGGAUGCUUGACUUUCAGGGAUGUGGCUAUAGAAUUCUCUUUGGAGGAGUGGAAAUGCCUGAACCCUGCACAGAGGGCUUUAUACAGGGCCGUGAUGUUGGAGAACUACAGGAACCUGGAGUCUGUGGAUGGAGUUUUGCUCUUGUUGCCCAGACUGGAGUGCAAUGGUGAGAUCUCAGCUCACCACAACCUCCUCCUCCCGGGUUCAAGCUAUUCUCCUGCCUCUGCCUCCCAAGUUGCUGGGACUACAGGUGCCUGUCACCAUGCCCAGGAUUGACUUCUAAGGACUCUUGGUACAUGAGGAAGAAACCCGGAAGGGGAAGAGGAAAGCAAAGGCGUCAGGAAUGGUUCUUCCUCAGGGUCUAUUGACAUUCAGGGAUGUGGCCAUAGAAUUCUCUCAGGAGGAGUGGAAAUGCCUGGACCCUGCUCAGAGGACUCUAUACAGAGAUGUGAUGUUGGAGAAUUAUAGGAACCUGGUCUCCCUGGGUAUUUUUUCUAAAUGUGAGAUCAAGGAAUUACCACCAAAAAAGGAGAGUAAUACAGGAGAAAUAUUCCAGACAGUAAUGUUGGAAAGACAUGAAAGCCACGACAUACAAGAUUUUUGCUUCAGAGAAACCCAGAAAAAUGUACAUGACUCUCAGUGUCUGUGGAAACAUGAUUGAAGACAUUAUAAGCGAGUGCGUGUGACCUAUAAGGAAAGUCUCAUUGGUAGAAGAGACAUGCAUGGGAGAAAGGAUGAUGCACAAAAGCAGCCUGUUAAAAAUCAGCUUGGAUUAAACCCGCAGUCACAUCUACCAGAACUGCAGCUAUUUCAAGCUGAAGGGAAAAUAUAUAAAUAUGAUCACAUGGAAAAAUCUGUCAACAGUAGUUCCUUAGUUUCCCCACCCCAACGUAUUUCUUCUACUGUCAAAACCCACAUUUCUCAUACAUAUGAAUGUAAUUUUGUGGAUUCAUUAUUCACACAAAAAGAGAAAGCAAAUAUUGGGACAGAACACUACAAAUGUAGUGAGCGUGGCAAGGCCUUUCAUCAAGGCUUACAUUUUACUAUACAUCAAAUAAUCCAUACUAAAGAGACGCAAUUUAAAUGUGAUAUAUGUGGCAAGAUCUUCAAUAAAAAAUCAAACCUUGCAAGUCAUCAAAGAAUUCAUACUGGAGAGAAGCCAUAUAAAUGUAAUGAAUGUGGCAAGGUCUUCCAUAAUAUGUCACACCUUGCACAGCAUCGCAGGAUUCAUACUGGAGAGAAACCAUAUAAAUGUAAUGAAUGUGGCAAGGUCUUUAAUCAAAUUUCACACCUUGCACAACAUCAAAGAAUUCAUACCGGAGAGAAACCUUAUAAAUGUAAUGAAUGUGGAAAGGUCUUCCAUCAAAUUUCACACCUUGCACAACAUCGGACAAUUCAUACUGGAGAAAAACCUUACGAAUGUAACAAAUGUGGCAAGGUGUUCAGUCGCAAUUCCUACCUUGUACAACAUCUGAUCAUUCAUACUGGAGAGAAACCUUACAGAUGUAAUGUAUGUGGAAAGGUCUUCCAUCAUAUUUCACACCUUGCACAACAUCAGAGAAUCCACACUGGAGAGAAACCUUACAAAUGUAAUGAGUGUGGCAAGGUCUUCAGUCACAAGUCAUCCCUAGUAAAUCACUGGAGAAUUCAUACUGGAGAGAAACCUUACAAAUGUAAUGAGUGUGGCAAGGUCUUCAGUCACAAGUCAUCCCUAGUAAAUCACUGGAGAAUCCACACUGGAGAGAAACCUUACAAAUGUAAUGAAUGUGGCAAGGUCUUCAGUCGCAAUUCAUACCUUGCCCAACAUCUGAUAAUUCAUGCCGGUGAGAAACCUUAUAAGUGUGAUGAAUGUGACAAAGCAUUCAGUCAAAAUUCACAUCUUGUACAACAUCACAGAAUCCAUACUGGAGAGAAACCUUACAAAUGUGAUGAAUGUGGCAAAGUCUUCAGUCAAAAUUCAUACCUUGCAUAUCAUUGGAGAAUUCAUACUGGAGAAAAAGCUUAUAAAUGUAAUGAAUGUGGGAAGGUCUUCGGUCUAAACUCAUCCCUAGCACAUCAUCGGAAAAUUCACACUGGAGAGAAACCUUUCAAAUGUAAUGAAUGUGGCAAAGCUUUUAGUAUGCGUUCAAGCCUCACUAAUCAUCAUGCGAUCCACACUGGAGAGAAACAUUUCAAAUGUAAUGAAUGUGGCAAACUCUUCCGCGACAAUUCAUAUCUUGUACGUCAUCAGAGAUUUCAUGCCGGAAAGAAAUCUAACACAUGUAAUUAAUGUGGCAGAGUGUUCAGUUAGCAUUAAAGCCUUGUAAGACAUACAAUAAUUUAUACUGGAGAAAAACUUUGCAAGUAUAAUGAAUGUAGCAGAGCCUUUAGUUUUUGUUCAAGGCUUAAUAACCGUUAGCUAGACCAUAGAGGACAGAAACUUUACUAAUGUACUGAAUGUGGCAAGGUCUUAAGGUAAAAUCUGAGACCAGGAUUCUUCAAAGAAUUCUUGCUGGUGAGAAACCUAACAAAUGUAAUGAAUGUGGCAAGGUCUUCUGGCACAAUUCUCACAUUGUACAAUAUUGCAAAAAUUCAUGCUUGAGAGAAACAAAAACACUGAGAGUGGGAAACCAUUAUGACUUCAAACAUUCAUCAACAUCAGAGAAUCCAUACUAAAGAGCAUUUAUAAUAAUUAUAUGUGAUAGAGAUUUUCCGCAGGCCAAAGUCUCACUAGGCAUCAAAAACUUUUUUGAUGAAACCAUACAAAUGUAACGUGCAUGCUUAAGCUUUUACCCAGGCAUCAAAACCGGAACAUCACAGGGUUUAUACUGGAGAGUAACUACACAAAGAUAAUGUAAUAAGCCUUUCAGUGUAAUAUUCAUGAUUUUGUCGUGAGAGAUCCACUCAAUAAAAACCAGGCAAAUGUA